GCCUUCUGAGCUCAGACAGCAGAAGGAUCACUGGGCUGGAAGCUCUAACAGGCAUUGCCAGCCUAGCUACCUGCAGUUUGAGGCAAGGGCAGGGUCACUUACCCUGCUGUCUGAAUGUCUCCUGGGACAACAGGAGGCUGCACUCACUGGCUGAGUUCAGACAGAAGAGGGAUCAUCGGACUGGAAGCUCUGGCAGGUAUGGCUAGCCUGGUUACCCGUAGUGAGAAUGGAGAGGGCCACCUGCCCAGCUACACAGAUGUUUCCCAGGACAACAGGAGGCUGUGUCCACUGACAGUUCAGACAGAAGUGGAACCACUGGACCGGAAGCUCUAGCAAGUGUUGCCCACCUGGCUACUAGUGAGCCUUGAAACCAGCGAAACAAUAAUCAAAGAGCAGUUCUGUCAAAGAAAACAACAUAAAUCAGGUACAGAAUUUCAGAGUGGGAUAUCAGAUCUUUAGUGUGAAGAUACAUCUACAUUAAACCAGGAAUCACUAGAACUGACAUUUGGACAAGAAAAUUUGGAAAAUUUUAAAACUGUGAAGGUUGAUCAUGGAAAUUAAAGAGGAAGGGGCAUCAGAAGAAGGGCAGCACUUUCUUCCUACAGCCCAGGCCAAUGAUCCCGGGGACUGUCAGUUCACAAGUAUCCAGAAGACUCCAAAUGAACCGCAGUUGGAAUUCAUCCUUGCAUGCAAGGAUCUCGUGGCUCCUGUCCGUGAUCGUAAACUGAAUACACUGGUGCAGAUCUCCGUAAUCCACCCCGUGGAGCAGAGUCUGACAAGAUACUCCAGCACCGAAAUUGUGGAGGGAACAAGGGACCCACUGUUUUUGACUGGUGUCACAUUCCCAUCUGAGUAUCCCAUCUAUGAGGAGACCAAAAUAAAACUAACAGUCUAUGAUGUCAAGGAUAAGUCUCAUGACACCGUUCGAACCAGUGUCCUACCAGAACAUAAGGAUCCCCCGCCAGAAGUUGGGCGAAGUUUCUUGGGCUAUGCCAGUUUUAAAGUGGGAGAGCUGCUGAAGUCAAAGGAGCAAUUGCUGGUCCUGAGCCUGAGAACUUCAGAUGGUGGCAAAGUGGUUGGCACCAUAGAAGUCAGUGUCGUGAAGAUGGGGGAGAUUGAGGAUGGGGAAGCCGACCACAUCACCACAGAUGUACAGGGACAAAAGUGUGCCCUGGUAUGUGAAUGUACAGCCCCGGAAAGUGUGAGCGGAAAAGAUAACUUACCUUUUUUGAAUUCAGUGUUAAAGAACCCAGUAUGUAAAUUAUAUAGAUUUCCCACAUCUGACAAUAAGUGGAUGCGAAUUCGAGAGCAGAUGUCAGAGAGCAUUCUUUCCUUUCAUAUUCCUAAGGAAUUGAUUUCCCUUCACAUUAAAGAAGAUUUGUGCAGAAACCAGGAGAUAAAAGAACUUGGUGAGCUUUCUCCACAUUGGGACAAUCUGCGAAAAAAUGUCCUUACUCACUGUGAUCAAAUGGUGAAUAUGUACCAAGACAUUCUGACAGAACUUAGCAAGGAAACAGGGUCCUCUUUCAAAUCAAGCAGCAGCAAAGGAGAGAAAACAUUAGAAUUUGUUCCAAUAAAUCUACAUCUGCAAAGAAUGCAGGUACACAGCCCUCACUUGAAAGAUGCUCUCUACGAUGUCAUCACUGUGGGAGCCCCAGCUGCCCAUUUUCAGGGAUUUAAGAAUGGUGGUCUUCGGAAGCUACUCCAUAGAUUUGAAACAGAAAGAAGAAAUACCGGAUACCAGUUUAUUUACUAUUCACCUGAAAACACAGCCAAAGCAAAGGAAGUUCUCAGCAACAUCAAUCAACUACAACCUCUUAUAGCAACCCAUGCAGACCUACUGCUUAAUUCUGCAAGCCAGCAUUCUCCAGACAGCUUGAAGAAUUCUUUAAAGAUGCUUUCAGAAAAAACAGAGCUUUUUGUACAUGCCUUCAAGGAUCAACUUGUCAGGAGUGCUCUUUUAGCACUCUACACUGCAAGGCCAGGAGGCAUUCUUAAGAAGCCACCCUCUCCUAAGAGCAGCACAGAGGAGAGCAGUCCCCAAGACCAACCCCCAGUGAUGAGAGGGCAGGACUCCAUACCACAUCAUUCAGACUAUGAUGAGGAAGAGUGGGACAGGGUGUGGGCCAAUGUGGGGAAGAGCCUGAACUGCAUUAUUGCUAUGGUGGACAAACUGAUUGAAAGAGAUGGUGGCAGUGAAGGCAGUGGCGGCAACAAUGAUGGAGAAAAGGAACCUUCAUUAACAGAUGCCAUUCCCUCUCACCCAAGAGAGGACUGGUAUGAACAGUUGUAUCCCCUCAUCCUUACCCUGAAGGACUGCAUGGGAGAAGUGGUGAACCGAGCCAAGCAGUCCCUGACAUUUGUGCUCCUUCAGGAACUUGCGUACAGCUUGCCCCAGUGUCUGAUGCUGACGCUAAGAAGAGACAUCGUCUUCAGCCAAGCACUUGCUGGAUUGGUUUGUGGUUUUAUCAUCAAAUUACAGACAAGUCUGUAUGACCCAGGCUUCCUACAGCAGCUUCACACAGUGGGGUUGAUAGUACAAUAUGAAGGACUGCUAAGUACAUACAGCGAUGAAAUUGGAAUGCUAGAGGACAUGGCCGUUGGCAUUUCCGAUUUAAAGAAAGUUGCAUUUAAAAUAAUUGAAGCCAAAUCCAAUGAUGUGUUGCCAGUUAUAACAGGAAGACGAGAACAUUACGUGGUAGAGGUCAAGCUUCCAGCCAGAAUGUUUGAGUCACUACCUCUACAGAUUAAAGAAGGACAGUUGCUUCAUGUGUAUCCAGUACUUUUUAAUGUUGGAAUCAAUGAACAGCAAACUCUGGCUGAAAGGUUUGGAGAUGUCUCUUUGCAAGAAAGUAUUAAUCAGGAAAACUUCGAACUUCUACAAGAAUAUUACAAGAUAUUUAUGGAAAAGAUGCCUCCUGAUUAUAUUUCACAUUUUCAGGAACAAAAUGAUUUAAAAGCAUUGCUAGAAAAUCUCCUUCAAAAUAUCCAAUCCAAAAAAAGAAAGAAUGUAGAAAUUAUGUGGCUGGCUGCAACGAUUUGCCGCAAACUGAAUGGUAUUCGUUUCACCUGUUGUAAAAGUGCCAAAGACAGGACAUCGAUGUCAGUGACACUUGAACAAUGCUCAAUCUUGAGAGAUGAGCACCAGUUACACAAGGACUUCUUUAUCCGAGCGCUGGAUUGCAUGAGAAGGCUUUGGUAUGAAGAUGAUGCUGGCCUCAUAAAUGAGUUAGGGAGGAGGAUUCCCUCUUUUUCUUUUGAUUGGAAUGGUUUCAGAAGAAACGGUACCAGUUCCUGUUUGUACCUCUGGUAGAUUUUGGCUGUGAAUACAUCUGGUCCUGGACUUUUUUUGAGAAGGAUGCCGCAUAGAGAAUGUACUGAAGAAUAUCAAAUGCAGAAAGUAUGCUUUCAACAUGCUACAGCUGAUGGCUUUCCCCAAGUACUACAGACCUCCAGAGGGGACUUAUGGAAAAGCUGACACCUAAGUUUACCAACAUGUUAAUAAACAGGAACACAAAUACAUUUCAGUUGGAUAAUCUUCACCUUGGUCUUUUUUGUUUGUUUUUAUUGUCAUGAAUUUGUGGUGGGGGAGAUGAUCACAGAUGUUUCCCAAAAUCUAGGAACUACUUCAAUUCAUCAUCAGCAUAUUGCUCUGAAAGAAAUCCAUUUUAAAAAAUCUUACAUGAUUCAGUACUGUCAUUUCUAGUUCUAAGCUUCUAUGUGUUGAGCCUAGCUGAUUGAGAUUGGUUCACAAAGUGUAAAUUUCAUUCAUGAGUAUUUAAAUGUUUCUGAGGAAACAUGGAUCAUUUCAAUAGGACUAGGGGUGAUUCACAGAGCACCACUCUCCAACCAAAUGGAAGAGAGGAGAGGGGGAAAAGGAACAUAUUUUUUUUGUGAUACAACUUAAUAGCCUAUGAGAACACAGUCAACCUGAGAAUCAAUGUAAGGGAUUUAAAAAAAAUGUGUAGCCACUCAAUUAGGUAGAGUUAACUCAUGAUCUGGAAUACUGAGGCAGUUUGCAGGUAUGUUCCACAAUGAUCUCUAUCAUCCAGUCAAGGUGUGACUCCUCCCUUGCAACAGGCAUAUGCAUGGAGUGAGUAAAGUGGUCAACAGACCUUUCAAAACCAUGGCAUCUUUUCAGAACUCUGACUUGGGUUGUGUGAUCUAGCUGUGAAUGUAGCAAUAUAGAACGUUUAAUAGAAUGAUAAGCAAAACACUGCAAUGAUCUAAAAUUACAAAUAAAAUAAAAAUGAACAACAUUUUGAUACCCAAAAUGAAAAUUCCCAUCAGCCUGAACUUUAUGUUGUGAAGUUCAUGAAUGUCAGUGAGGUAUCUCUGAGAUGUUUCUUAGCAGUCAUCCUGGUGUAAGCAUGCAGUUAUGGCAUAGGUUUGUGUGUGUUAAUAAGCCUUUAAAACAUAUGCAACCACAACAAAUGAUAAAGUAAAACAAUUAUUUUCUGUUGCCCUGAAUAUCAAACUUGCCCUUGCCCUUACUCAGCAAAAUAACAUUUAUAAGUUUUCCAAAAUCCCAAAGUAGAAGUUUCCUUAAAAAAAUCAUCUUGUAUAAUACCAGUAUUCAAACAUGGGUAAGGUUAAUCACCCCCAAUCACUCAGGAGAUAGUUGCAGAAUUUGAAUUACAAUCUCUUCUUACUUUCCUAGCCUGUGGCUUGUCACUUCUCCAAAUUGCCAUGCUAAAUAUGCAUGAAAAUUGAGGGAGAAUGCUAGUUAAAAAGAAAUUAGGAUUUAUCACUGGAAUUGAAACUAAGAGUACAAAAGUCUGAACGAAUGAAACUUUUCUCCAAAUUUUACAAAUUCUUGUUCCUUUCUCAUUAGAAGAGCAUGCUAUCCAAAGCAUAAAUCUCCCUUGAAAAUAACAGAGGCUUCUUAAGCCCUCUCUUAGCUAUGAUCAAUGGAUGAUAUUAUGCUUCCCAUAGCUAAUGUGAUAGCUCCUUGCCUAGGAUUCCUGUUGAAAUAAGGAUUCUAGCCCCAUGUUAAGUUUUUCAAAUUACUACAAAUUUUAGAUAAGCAUUUGGAGCUUUUUAUACUAGAAUUAUCAAUUUUUUAUUUUAGCUAAUUACCUGUGGGCAUUAUACUUGAGGCAGGUACCAAACUACUUACAGCCUUUUUAAUGAAAAUGUGCUGUGUACUUUGAAUCCAUUCAUAGACAAAAUUACCUUGAUGUUCUCUUAACUCAUUCUUUAUUUUAGUGAUUAAAUACAACCUUUGAGUUGUUCAAUAUCAUUUGAAAAUGGUAGGAUUUGUGGUUAUUUUCAUUACCCUAUUAGAUUUAAGAUAGGCUGGGAUGACAGAGGCCUCCUUGAAUAGCUAUGAAGCCUCAUUCAGCAUAUCAAAUGGUAGUCUGAGUUCUAAGAAACCUUAAGUAAUUUAUCAUUCUGUAAAUACUCUUAUAAGCAAUAAUUUUUAUUUGUAUUUUUGAAAACAAACUACUUAAAUAUGGAAAAAUAUUAACUGGAAAGCCAGCAGUAGGGUUUUCUAUUUUUAAAAGACAUUUCAAGGAUUUCCUGUAAUCCCAGCACUUUGGGAGCCAAGGUGGAUAGAUCACCUGAGGUCAGGAAUUGGAGAUCAGCCUGGCCAACAUGGUGAAACCCCAUCUCUACUAAAGAUACAAAAAUUAGCUGGAUGUGGUGGCACACACGUGUAAUCCCAGCUACUUGGGAGGCUGAGGCAAGAGAAUCGCUUGAACCCCGGAGGCGGAGGUUGCAGUGAGCUGAGAUCAUGCCAUUGCACUCCAGCCUGGGUGAAAAGAGCGAAACUCCAUCUUUAAAUAAGUAAAUAAAUGAAUAAUAUAGAAGUCUCAAAUUAUAGUGCUUACUGUAAUACAAAUGCUUAUGAAUUUUCAUUCAUUACCAUAGUCAUCUGCAUUUCCUUAUAGAAAGCCUGUACUGGUGCAAACUUCUAAAAGUGGAUUUCAUCAAGAAAAUGUGUUUCAUAGAGACAACAAUAUUGCUUUUUUCCUGAGAGGCAGUUCAUUCUUAAACAACCACUUCACUAUUUCUUAAGUUAUUAAGGCUAAAUCAAAGAGCAAAUGUUAAAGUGUUUAAAUCUCUCUUGAACAAACACAGCCACAGUCAUGCUAUUCUAUCUAUAUUUUCACUUAAAAGAUACACCAGCAGACCUAUUUUAGGAGGUCAUAUUGAGCCAAAAAAUGAACUGAGCAAAUGACAUUUCCAAACUCUUUUUUUGCUCAAAAAUAAUAUGUUCCCCUUUGAUAUUAAAUGCAGAUAUCAAUUCUGGAUUAGCUAUUUACUGAGCCCUAGGAAAAACAUAUUUAAAGACAAGGAAACCAUUCAUUUACAUCUCAUAUCAUUGCUUUUUGCUUUUAAAUAUCGCCUUGAGGUUUGUCUACACUCUGCCAAAACAAUCCCUGAACAUAAGUUUGGUCAGCCUCAUAAUUCAGUGAGUCGAGCAACCAUUUGUUCCAAGUGAUAAAUUGUACUAAAUGACAAACUGCCCAAUCAGGGCAGAGCUCCAUGGACCCAGCCUCCAGCCCUUAUUUUAUAAGACUAACCCCUCUUCUGAAAAACUCUGAAGGCUUAAAAGCUAGCAUUUGGAUGGAGGAUACUUCCUUUUUAUCCUUCAGCUAUGUAUGGCACUUUACAUAAAAUAAGAGGUAAAAAAGGAGAGAAACUGAUGUGUAUAAAGUAAUGCCUUUCUUCCCAAGCAAAUCAAACCUCUCCCUAUGUAAAAGUUGAUAGUGUACCAAGAGACACAAUACCACUGGUGGGCUGGAACUAGCUCGUUCUGAUGCAUAAAAGUUGAUAAUUAAAGUACCAGAAAUUUUGUAAGCUAGUUGUUAAACAUUACCAUUAUUAAAUAUGAAAUUAUAAAACACAGUGGAAUACAUUAAAAACCAAUGUAAUAAUCAAAACAUACCACUUCCCAAUUAUUUUACUACCUUAUACUAUUUAUUAGUACUCUUGAGUCUAUUUAGGUCUAUUACAUCUUUACAGUGAAAACAGGAUACAAUAUUGUGCUACUGUGGGUCUCUUCCUGACUGCAGAUUCAGUAACAUGGUGUUCGUAGCUUGAAACUGUCCACAGUGGGAGUAUUUAACACCAUAGAAACUGGCUGGCAAAUGCUACAAACUAGCAAUUUUAAUUCCUGGAAAGGCAAUUGUUGAGCAUUUACCAGCACACAAUGAAUGCCAUAUUCUUUUUUUUUUAUUAGGAAAUAAAUUAUUGGAGGCAGUAUAAAAUUAUUUAAAAAGUAUCAAAUGCAAUCCCUUAUCUUCAGAUGGCUAUAAUUUUGGUUAUAUAAAUGUUUUGGUUUUUACCUUCUUUAAAGACUCCUAUUAGGUUAAAAGUCAUAUUUGAUGACUAUAUUUUAUUCAUAAUUAAAUUAUUAAAUCACCUUUUCUCCUGAUAAUGCUUUGCCAGAGAAUUCUUAGCAAUUCAACUGUAGUCUAAGCAAUAACUCAGGGCUAAAUUCAGGGAACUGUUAGCCCAAUCAGAUAUCACUAAAAAUGUACUUCACCAUCUAUUUUGGAGUUUAUAAUUUUGGCAUUUGCUAAAAGUAGGAAAAACAGUAACAUAUUACUGUGCCCAGAUUCUAAUAAAUAUAGCUCAAUUGAAACCAAAACUGUUACAUUAAACAAAUUACACUCUGGCACUAUGCUAAAUCACCACAGAUGUUUUAGGUGUUUGAUUUCCAAGCAGGAUGGUAUAUCAUUUGUUUGGUUCAAUAUAUGAGGCACCAUUUGUAGUCUUUUAGGAAAUAAAUUAGCUUUUAUCACAGAUUUAGGAAACUUGUCUAAAAAAACUGUGAUCAUCAGUUACAGAGGGAAGGAAACAUAUUGAACACAAGGCAUCAUAGUAGCUGGAGGCCUUAAAAAUUAUGCACGACCAAAAAGAAUGAUUUGGUGAGAGAUGUGUAGCUGAUUGACAAUUUUAGUGUGAAUUCAUAUUCAUUUAACCCAGCAGCAAUCUACAUAAGCUAUGCUUUUUCCCACCUGUAUUUAUGUUUCUUAGCUUAUAAAGUCCCAAUAUAUUAUAUCUUUUGUUGCUUUGGCAGUUUUAAUUUAGAGCUCUGCGUUCACAGAGAUGCCACCUAUAGCAAAAACUAUCUUUAAGAAUUGGAAAAUAAAAUGAAUGUUUUAGAUAAAAUAUUGCAAGCCAUUAUGUGUAGAGUUAAUGUAUGGAAAUUUGCAUUUGUUUUUCUGAAUCAUGGUGUACAUUAAUCACUCAUUGAAUUCUAUUUCUAAGCAAAUAAGAGAAUCAAACAUUUCUAAAAGGAACAUAUGUCUUGCUAUUAAUAACAAGGAGACAGGAAAAAUAGUAAGGUAAUAUAAGCAAAAAAAAAAAUGUAAUGAAUUUAGCUAUCCUAAAUUGGAAUUUUUACAGAUUGCAUGCAUACUUAGAAUUUUAAAUUUUUAAAAGAUUUACAAUUGAGUAUGGUACCCACAGAGAGUGAGUACCAAGGGAAGGAAGACCUAAUACAAGUGAUGUUGCCUGAUAAAUCACAUCUUGCCAAAAAAAAUAUAUUUUAGUAAAUACAGUUCUUUAGGAAGAAAAAUGUUGCCCUUUCACACUCACAGUGUAAAUACAUUCAUAAUAUUCCUUCAAUCAUCUAAAUUACCGCCAGGUCAUGAAAGGACGCGAUCAAUGAUGACCUAUUGCACUCACAGGUAACAUUGACUCAAAUUUUGGCAAUAUUGCUAUAUUAUCUAGAUAAUUCUUGUGAUGUUUUUAUGUCACUAUCAACAUUAAAAAUAUUUUGUUAAACAACUAUGAAACUUUCAAAAGUUUGCAUAUAACUGUAUGGGCACUCUCAUUUCACUGCAUACAUACAAUACUUUGUAUACACAUACUUCUCGUGUGGAUAUUUUAUAAUUUUAUUUAAUCUAACAUUUAACUUUUAGGUUUUUGUGGUACUCAUCUGAAAGGUUGGCAUUUGUUUUCUUUUUAUGUUAUAUAUGUAUUUUAGAUGAAUCAAUAAUGUGUAUUCCUAGAAAUUUUUUCUAGGCAUAAAUAGAUCAUUUUAUGUUGGCAUUUAAGAGAUAUCAUUUUUGUUUUAUUGUUCUGUGUAAACCAUAUUCAUUGUACACUGUGUGUAUAUUUUUGUUUAAAUAAAUGAUUUUUAUUUUUUA